AGUCCCCACUGCUCAGCACUAGGCCGGCAGAAUCUGAGCGAUGUCUUCCACACUCCCUGCCCUGCUCUGCGUCGGGCUGUGUCUGAGUCAGAGGAUCAGCGCCCAGCAGCAGACUCUCCCAAAACCGUUCAUCUGGGCCGAGCCCCAUUUCAUGGUUCCAAAGGAAAAGCAAGUGACCAUCUGUUGCCAGGGAAAUUAUGGGGCUGUUGAAUACCAGCUGCACUUUGAAGGAAGCCUUUUUGCCGUGGACAGACCAAAACCCCCUGAGCGGAUUAACAAAGUCCAAUUCUACAUCCCGGACAUGAACUCCCGCAUGGCAGGGCAAUACAGCUGCAUCUAUCGGGUUGGGGAGCUCUGGUCAGAGCCCAGCAACUUGCUGGAUCUGGUGGUAACAGAAAUGUAUGACACACCCACCCUCUCGGUUCAUCCUGGACCCGAAGUGAUCUCGGGAGAGAAGGUGACCUUCUACUGCCGUCUAGACACUGCAACAAGCAUGUUCUUACUGCUCAAGGAGGGAAGAUCCAGCCACGUACAGCGCGGAUACGGGAAGGUCCAGGCGGAGUUCCCCCUGGGCCCUGUGACCACAGCCCACAGAGGGACAUACCGAUGUUUUGGCUCCUAUAACAACCAUGCCUGGUCUUUCCCCAGUGAGCCAGUGAAGCUCCUGGUCACAGGCGACAUUGAGAACACCAGCCUUGCACCUGAAGACCCCACCUUUCCUGCAGACACUUGGGGCACCUACCUUUUAACCACAGAGACGGGACUCCAGAAAGACCAUGCCCUCUGGGAUCACACUGCCCAGAAUCUCCUUCGGAUGGGCCUGGCCUUUCUAGUCCUGGUGGCUCUAGUGUGGUUCCUGGUUGAAGACUGGCUCAGCAGGAAGAGGACUAGAGAGCGAGCCAGCAGAGCUUCCACUUGGGAAGGCAGGAGAAGGCUGAACACACAGACUCUUUGAAGAAUGACCAUGAGACACAGUGGCCAUGGGUGGAUCUGAAAGCUGGUGUUGAGCCUGGGCGGCGUGAGCUCUGUGUUGGACCCACGGAGGAGGGAGUCACUGCAGGGAAAGAGGGACACUGGCAUUCCAUUUGUCAGAGCAUCCCGGACGAUGCAGAGGGUGGGAGAACUACAUGCUAAAUUUCUUUUUUUUUUUUUUUGAG